AGACUCCAUCUGCCCGGGGCCGCUAAGGGAGCGCAAGGUCAAGUUCGCCUUGGCCCCGCCUCCAGCUCAGGUACUAGGGGAUCUAGACCUGAGGCUGCCCGGGCCGGAGGCAGCCUUGAGUCCCGAGACCAAACGUCGUUUCCCUCUCGGACCUCGGGCGCCGGGCCGCGCGCUGACCGACAGCCCCUGCUAGGCCCAGCAGGUCCCCUAGUCCCCCGCAGUCCCCCGAGACUCGCCGAGCGCCGUUGCUGAGCCCUGCAAAUAGCAGCUACCUGCUUCAGCCUAGAUCCUGCCAUGAAGCGGACUGCUGCUCCCUGGCUCCCACUCUGAUCUGCUUUUCACUCUUGCCUUGUCUCCCAAUUAAUAAGCAGGGUGGCCACUGCAACAGGUGUGGAUGUGCCUGACAAGAUGAAGAGCCGAAUACCUGUGGUGCUCCUGGCCUGUGGCUCCUUUAACCCCAUCACCAACAUGCACCUGCGCAUGUUUGAGGUGGCCAGAGAUCACCUACACCAAACAGGAAUGUACCAGGUCAUCCAGGGUAUCAUCUCUCCUGUCAACGACACCUAUGGGAAGAAAGACCUCGCAGCUUCUCAUCACCGAGUGGCCAUGGCCCGGCUGGCCCUGCAGACAUCCGACUGGAUCCGGGUGGACCCUUGGGAGAGUGAGCAGGCACAGUGGAUGGAGACAGUGAAGGUGCUGAGAUAAAGAAACUGAGGCUCAGAGAGGCUACGUUAAUCACGGUCACACACAAAUAGGACGUGGAGCUCCCAUCUGUGGAGCUCUGAAGCCAUGCUUAUGGCCAUCUUCAAAACAGGGAUCUGCAGGCUGGGAACAUGAUGUGGCUGGCUUUACACCUCCCACAGUUGCCCUCCAAUCUUUCCUGAAGACCAGUGGGACUGCUGAGGACACCAAGAACAUGCCCCCAGGGUCAAUCCACAGGCCCAAGGUACCACUCAGGCAGGCAGCAAGAAGCAGUUAAUGGUCAUGCCCCAUAGAGGCGCAGUGGAAGUCCCUGGCAAAUGCAUGUUGUAUUGGAAGUAAUUAUUUCCACAACAAAGUUCAGAGAUCCAGCUAAUAUUCAAAGUAGGGUCAACCUGAACUAGGACCUUCAAGGCAUCAUCACAGCAAACUGCUCAGAUCUCCACCCCAGAUGGAAGGCCCAGACCAUGGCAAGGCACUCUUCUCGACCCCUGCAGCUGUGCCUGAGCUGAAGCUUCUCUGUGGGGCAGACGUCUUGAAGACCUUCCAGACCCCCAACCUCUGGAAGGAUGCGCACAUCCAGGAAAUAGUGGAGAAGUUUGGCUUGGUGUGCGUGGGCCGAGUAGGUCACGACCCAAAAGGUUACAUCGCAGAAUCUCCCAUCCUACGGAUGCACCAGCACAACAUUCACCUGGCCAAGGAGCCUGUGCAGAAUGAGAUCAGUGCCACAUACAUCAGGCGAGCCUUGGGCCAAGGGCAGAGCGUAAAGUACCUGAUUCCCGAUGCUGUCAUCACGUACAUCAAGGACCAUGGCCUCUACACCAAGGGCAGUACCUGGAAAGGCAAAAGCACCCAGAGCACUGAGGGCAAGACAAGCUAGGGAGGGGGGACUCAGCACCCACACCUCCUCCAACAAGCUCCUGCUGGGGAGAGGGCUGUUAAGGUUUCUGUUUUACUUUGGUUUUUGCUUCUCCAUUUUUCAUUUGCUUUAUUUCUACAGUGAUUCUACUUCUGAGGAGUCUUCUGUCCCAGGAAGAGAUACCUUCUUUACAGGAGAGGAAAGGUCUAAAUCACAAGGAUAGACAUUUAUCAAAGAAGUUAAAAUGGUGUGGCAGGUCAUUAGGAUUAGGCAGAAUCUCUCAGAGCUGCUGGACAAGGAGGUCUACUUAUUUUGUGUGGAUGGUAAUUAUGGCAUGCACGCUGAAUGCAGUUCUGAGCAUGGCAGCGGCCCCUGAGGGUCAGAUCAGAAUUGCCCACAAUGUGUUUUUUAACUAGGACCAGGUGCAGCAUGCUAGUCUUGAUUGGAAAGAUUUGACAGGAUGCUAAUUACUGAACAGUGGGUUUUGUCAACGCCCUGGUUUCAGAAUAUGAACUGAGGAGUCAAACAGUUGGAAACAGCACAUUGCUGAUUUACACUGGAUCUUGCCUUAGAAACCAUUGUCUGCCUGCCUAACCAGCUUUUCAUAAAAUUUAAACAAAACUCUUUCUACGUAGUGAUCCUCAAGCAAUAUUUUUGAUACAGCAAGUGUCAAACUUGCUAUAGCAUAAAAGCCGGGGCUCCUGAUUUCCAGGUUUCUAAAAAGGAACUGAGGUAAAACAGAUGCCUGACCGUUUUAAAGGAUCUUUUUUAAUGUUUUAUGACUGCCUGUCUGUUUGAAUACUGGCAAAGGGAUAAAUAAUAAAUUGACAUCAAAAAGUA